GUCUCUAGCUAACACGCACGGCGGGGACAGUUUAGGCCUCCGCGCACCGUUCGCCGGGAGUCUUGCAGUUUGCUUGGUGCAGGGAAGGCGGGCGCGGAGGUUCUAUCUGUUUCUUCCUCCUUCGUGAGCAGCAUGGACGUGCUAGCGGAGGAGUUUGGGAACCUGACUCCGGAGCAGCUGGCGGCGCCGAUCCCGACUGUAGAGGAAAAAUGGAGGCUGCUUCCAGCAUUUUUAAAGGUGAAAGGCCUUGUGAAACAGCAUAUAGAUUCAUUUAACUAUUUCAUUAAUGUAGAGAUAAAGAAGAUAAUGAAAGCCAAUGAAAAGGUUACAAGUGACGCUGACCCUAUGUGGUACUUAAAAUAUCUUAAUAUCUAUGUUGGGCUUCCUGAUGUUGAAGAAAGCUUCAAUGUAACUAGACCAGUGUCCCCUCAUGAGUGCCGUUUGAGAGACAUGACAUACUCUGCCCCUAUUACAGUGGAUAUUGAAUAUACCCGAGGCAGCCAGAGGAUCAUCCGCAAUGCCUUACCUAUCGGCAGAAUGCCCAUAAUGCUACGUAGUUCAAACUGUGUUCUUACAGGAAAAACGCCAGCAGAAUUUGCCAAACUGAACGAAUGUCCCUUAGAUCCAGGUGGCUACUUCAUUGUUAAAGGAGUAGAAAAAGUUAUUCUUAUCCAAGAGCAGCUGUCUAAGAACAGGAUCAUCGUGGAGGCUGAUAGAAAAGGGGCUGUUGGAGCUUCAGUUACCAGCUCUACCCAUGAGAAAAAAAGCAGAACCAAUAUGGCUGUGAAACAAGGACGAUUUUAUUUGAGGCAUAAUACUUUGUCAGAAGAUAUACCCAUUGUCAUCAUAUUUAAGGCCAUGGGUGUUGAGAGUGACCAGGAAAUUGUGCAGAUGAUUGGAACAGAGGAGCACGUGAUGGCUGCAUUUGGGCCCAGUCUGGAAGAGUGCCAGAAAGCUCAGAUUUUCACACAGAUGCAGGCAUUAAAAUAUAUAGGGAACAAAGUAAGAAGGCAAAGGAUGUGGGGAGGUGGACCAAAGAAAACCAAAAUAGAAGAAGCAAGAGAGCUCCUGGCUUCCACCAUUCUGACCCAUGUCCCAGUUAAGGAAUUCAAUUUCCGAGCCAAAUGUAUCUAUACUGCAGUGAUGGUGCGAAGAGUUAUUCUGGCCCAAGGAGAUAAUAAAGUUGACGACAGAGAUUAUUAUGGUAACAAGCGACUGGAAUUGGCAGGACAGCUUUUAUCUCUUCUUUUUGAAGACUUGUUCAAAAAAUUUAAUUCUGAAAUGAAAAAGAUUGCCGACCAGGUGAUUCCUAAGCAAAGAGCAGCCCAGUUUGAUGUUGUCAAACACAUGCGCCAAGACCAGAUCACCAAUGGCAUGGUGAAUGCUAUUUCUACCGGAAAUUGGUCUUUAAAGAGAUUUAAAAUGGACCGCCAGGGUGUAACCCAAGUGCUGUCUCGCUUGUCAUAUAUAUCCGCACUGGGCAUGAUGACAAGAAUCUCUUCCCAGUUUGAAAAAACGAGAAAAGUGAGUGGUCCUCGCUCCCUCCAGCCAUCUCAGUGGGGAAUGCUGUGUCCUUCGGACACUCCUGAAGGAGAGGCAUGUGGUUUGGUUAAAAACUUGGCCCUUAUGACACACAUCACAACUGAUAUGGAAGAUGGACCCAUUGUUAAAUUAGCCAGUAACUUGGGAGUAGAAGAUGUGAAUUUAUUAUGUGGGGAAGAGCUCUCUUACCCAAAUGUGUUUCUUGUCUUUCUUAAUGGUAACAUCUUAGGUGUCAUUCGAGACCACAAAAAGCUAGUGAAUACAUUUCGACUCAUGAGAAGAGCAGGAUAUAUCAAUGAAUUUGUUUCCAUCUCAACAAAUCUUACAGAUCGAUGUGUCUAUAUUUCUUCUGAUGGGGGAAGGCUAUGCAGACCCUACAUAAUUGUCAAGAAACAGAAGCCAGCAGUCACAAAUAAACAUAUGGAAGAGCUGGCCCAAGGGUACAGGAAUUUUGAAGAUUUCUUACAUGAGAGUCUGGUUGAAUAUUUAGAUGUGAAUGAAGAAAAUGAUUGUAACAUUGCACUGUACGAACACACAAUUAAUAAAGACACCACCCACUUGGAGAUUGAACCCUUCACUCUUCUCGGCGUGUGUGCUGGACUUAUCCCAUACCCUCACCAUAACCAGUCACCGAGAAACACUUAUCAGUGUGCCAUGGGGAAACAAGCCAUGGGUACUAUAGGAUACAACCAGCGAAACAGAAUUGAUACUCUCAUGUAUCUACUAGCAUAUCCACAAAAACCCAUGGUUAAGACAAAAACCAUUGAAUUGAUAGAAUUUGAGAAACUGCCAGCUGGACAGAAUGCAACAGUUGCUGUGAUGAGCUAUAGUGGCUAUGAUAUUGAAGAUGCUCUUGUUUUAAACAAGGCCUCUUUAGACAGAGGCUUUGGGCGUUGCCUUGUAUAUAAAAAUGCUAAAUGUACGUUGAAACGAUACACCAAUCAGACUUUUGAUAAAGUGAUGGGGCCCAUGUUGGAUGCUGCUACAAGGAAACCUAUCUGGCGACAUGAAAUCUUAGAUGCAGAUGGUAUUUGUUCUCCAGGUGAGAAAGUAGAAAACAAACAAGUGCUUGUAAAUAAGUCCAUGCCCACAGUGACUCAGAUUCCUUUGGAAGGAAGUAAUGUACCACAGCAACCACAGUACAAAGAUGUACCCAUAACCUACAAAGGAGCAACAGACUCAUAUAUUGAAAAAGUGAUGAUAUCUUCAAAUGCUGAAGAUGCUUUUCUGAUCAAAAUGCUGCUGAGACAGACAAGGCGUCCAGAAAUUGGAGACAAAUUCAGCAGUCGUCAUGGGCAAAAAGGUGUUUGUGGCUUGAUCGUCCCCCAGGAAGACAUGCCAUUUUGUGAUUCUGGCAUCUGUCCGGACAUCAUCAUGAACCCACACGGCUUCCCAUCACGAAUGACGGUGGGGAAGCUCAUUGAGCUGCUGGCUGGCAAGGCCGGUGUGCUGGACGGCAGAUUCCACUACGGCACUGCGUUUGGAGGCAGUAAAGUGAAGGAUGUGUGUGAGGACCUCGUUCGCCAUGGUUAUAACUACUUGGGGAAAGACUAUGUUACAUCCGGCAUCACAGGAAAUAAGGCACAUUUUUGGCCAGGUGUUGACCAGAAAGUGCAAAACCAUAGGAUCAAUUUGGUGGACCUUCGUGAACAUAAUUUGUACUGAAAGAAUUGGAUGGGUUAUAUCCUGCUUGCCGUAGACAAUGGUUAGUCUAUAUCCCAGUCCACACUGCCUUCCCCUAUGCCCCCAGCCAGAGUUUUCCUUUCUUUGCCAUUUAUUUCAGUGACAAAAUCUGAGAAGCACUGUUUAGUUGAAAAUUCCCGAGGGCAUUUAAAUAUAUCACCACCAGCUUUCACUUUUUGUUCAUUCUUGAACAUAGAUAGGUAGGAGGAAAAAUUGCAUAUAGCUUUACUCUGUGGAUGAUGGAAUAGCAUUGGGUAACCGAGUGUCAUAAAUUCUACCAUGAGCAACCCUACCAUUGAGGAAUAGAAUCAUUCACUGUUAGAGCAGGAAAGAAUCUUGUUCUGACCGCCUUCUUGUACAACUAAGAACACUCAGCUAGAGAGGUCAUGUAAUUACUUUACUAUGUGACAAAACCAAGACAAGGACAGGGUCUCUUAAUACCCUCUCCAUUGUGCCUUCCACUCCACUCUGUGUCUUCCAAGAACCAGGUUGUGCUGAAGUCAGCAGAAUGGCCUGAUGACCACAAAAGCCUUGGCUCAGGAUGCUGAGAGUGUGAUCAGGGACACCGAGCAAACAGUGGCCAAGCUUUUCCUUUGCCUCUCUGCUGUGUCUGUUGUUUCCUUUACUUUUUCUACUUUUACAUCAUGCUGUACCCCAGAGUUUACUUGUUCCAAAUCAGACCAGUGUUGCAGGGAGAGCCCUGGAUUUGAACCCUCACUGCACCACUCACCAGUUCUUAUCUGACCUGUCGGGCGCUCUGUGUCCAUUUCUUCAUCUUCAAAAUAGAGGUGACAGUUCUUCCUCCCUGGAUCGUUGUGUGGAUUAAGUAGCACAUGGUAGUUGCUUCCUUCCCUUUGAAGAAGAAAGUUUGAGGCAGUUAAAAAAAAAUUUUUUAAGACAUCAGUUCUCUGGUUGUUCUUGCUCCAGAUUAAUGAGAAAAGGUUUCUUCUGUCAAAGUACUUAUAUAUUCACCCUCUUCUUAAACUCUUACUACAGACUUUCUAAAGAUUCAUUGAAGCAGUUAUGUAAUAGACAUUUAUUGAGUACCAGUUGUGUGCCAGGCAGGGUCACAGGUGCUGGAGCCACCGUGACAAAGGAGACAAAGUGCUUAUCCUUGCAGAGUUACUUCUAGUGGGGAAGACAGGCAAUAAUCCGAGAGAUAAUAAAUGUACACCACGGUAUCAAAAGGGGCAAGUGCGCCAAAGGGUCAGGUUGAGACAGGGCCGGAGUGACGAUGCCAGGUGGGAGGAGGACUUCUUUAGAUGUGGUAUUCAGUGAAAGUCUCUCUGAGCAGGUGAAAUGUUUGACAGAGCCAUAUGAAUACCUGGCGGGAGAGUGUUUCAGGCAAAGGAAACGGUAAGUCAGAGGCCCCAAGAGAGGAACAGGCUUGCUCCAUUUGAGGAGUAAUGAAGAGGCCAGUGUUGUUGGAGUAGAGUGACUGGCGGGACACUGGAAUAGGAAACAGUGAGGUGUGCAGGAACUGGAGUAUGUCUCACCAUGUGGCCAUAAUAUAGAAUGUUGGCAAUACAGAUUCCAAGUAUGAUGGGAAACCAUUGGUGAGUUCAGGACAGAAGAAUGACCUAUUGUGAUUUACAUUUUAGAAGGCAUCCCCCUGACUUUUUAUGCAAAGAAUAGAUUGUUGAGGGAUGAGAGUGGAAGCAGGGAGAUUAAUUAGAAGAUUAUCUGUGGUAGCCCAAGCAAGAAAGGAUGGUGGCCUGACCAGGGAGGUCAUCCUGAAGGAGAGAUCAUCCCAUACACACUGUUUCCCAACCUGUUUAAAUGUCUAUUUCUUUGUAAAGCCAUUUAUCUUUAAAUAUAGCUAUGGUACUUUUCAUAUUUUUACAACUAGUCUUUUCAUUCACUACAGACUGAAAAUCAUUCUUAUCCAGUCAGUCAUAAAUGAGUAAGGACCUGCCAGUGAUGGGUCCAAAGGCUGUCUCUUGUUAGCCCAAACUUAGUUUCUUAACCCACAACAA